AGUCGCCUAGCAGGUCCUCUACCGGCUUAUUCCUGUGCCGGAUCUUCAUCGGCACAGGGGCCACUGAGACGUUUCUGCCUCCCUCUUUCUUCCUCCGCUCUUUCUCUUCCCUCUCGUUUAGUUUGCCUGGGAGCUUGAAAGGAGAAAGCACGGGGUCGCCCCAAACCCCUUCUGCUUCUGCCCAUCACAAGUGCCACUACCGCCAUGGGCCUCACUAUCUCCUCCCUCUUCUCCCGACUAUUUGGCAAGAAGCAGAUGCGCAUUUUGAUGGUUGGAUUGGAUGCUGCUGGCAAGACAACCAUUCUGUAUAAACUGAAGUUAGGGGAGAUAGUCACCACCAUUCCUACCAUUGGUUUUAAUGUGGAAACAGUAGAAUAUAAGAACAUUUGUUUCACAGUAUGGGAUGUUGGUGGUCAAGAUAGAAUUAGGCCUCUCUGGAAGCAUUACUUCCAGAAUACCCAGGGUCUUAUUUUUGUGGUAGAUAGCAACGAUCGUGAAAGAAUUCAGGAAGUAGCAGAUGAGCUGCAGAAAAUGCUUCUGGUAGAUGAAUUGAGAGAUGCAGUGCUGCUACUUUUUGCAAACAAACAGGAUUUGCCAAAUGCUAUGGCCAUCAGUGAAAUGACAGAUAAACUAGGGCUUCAGUCUCUUCGUAACAGAACAUGGUAUGUUCAAGCCACUUGUGCAACACAAGGAACUGGUCUGUAUGAAGGACUUGACUGGCUGUCAAAUGAGCUUUCAAAACGUUAAAUGAAAUUGGAUAUCUAACCAAGGACAUGUUUGAUAAAAUUGGUCUAGGCUUGUUACAACAAAAUUAGUUUGUAUCUUGGUUAUUAAACAGUAUCUGGGACUGGUUUGGGCAGAAUAUUAAACUUAUUUUGUUGCCAAUUAUUGUUUACCGAGUAUAAUGUUGCUAUUUAGCAAUGUGCUUGGUUUUAAAGAAAUUCUCCUUGGGAAAAAAGUAUCCUCUUUUAAUUUUACUUCCCAUAAGCGUAAAUGCCUGGACAUAGCUCUUGUGCAACCUUUAAAUAAAUUGUUUUGAGUGUUUUUUGAGCCCCAGACAAAUAAUGUUUUAAAGUUAUCCCCUUGCUACUUUACUGAUACCUUUAUCAUUCCUGAGACAGUUUGCUAAUUUAAAAAUGUAGCAUUCCAUUUGUAUUUAUUUCUCUCCCUUGCCAAAAAGAUUUUCUAAUACUGCUUGUACCAGCCAGAGAAAGAUCCAAAACACUACUCAGCUCUCUUGCACUGAGGAAAUUUUUCCCCCUACAUUGACUCCUGGCCUACAUCAGCCAAACUUAACCUUGGUGGGGUUUGGAUUUGAUAGCCAAUUAGUUCUGUGCUGGUUGCAAAGAAUUGAUAUUUAGAUGGUUUUUAAUACUCAGCAGAUUGUCUUCCUUUAUAUUGUGUCUUUUUUAUGUUGCAUGUUGCUUUUGUUAUCAGCCUGAUUUUUUGCUCAGUAUAUGAUAGUUCUGCUGAUGUUUUGUUUAUUGGGCAGACAUAUCUUCAUUAAGAGUUUUUGGAAAACUCAUCAAAUUCGAUGAAUACAUUUUCUUCAUAACCCAUUUGGAAUUAUUCCUAAUAAAAUGAUAAAAUACGUAA